GUCCCCGCCCCACAGCCAACCUCCCGGGCACCGUUGCCCGCCCGGGGCCCGCUACCGGCCCAGGCCCCGCCUCGCGAGUCCUCCUCCCCGGGUGCCUUCCCGCAGCCCGCUCGGCCCAGAGGGUGGGCGCGGGGCUGCCUCUACCGGCUGGCGGCUGUAACUCAGCGACCUUGGCCCGAAGGCUCUAGCAAGGACCCACCGACCCCAGCCGCGGCGGCGGCGGCGCGGACUUUGCCCGGUGUGUGGGGCGGAGCGGACUGCGUGUCCGCGGACGGGCAGCGAAGAUGUUAGCCUUCGCUGCCAGGACCGUGGACCGAUCCCAGGGCUGUGGUGUAACCUCAGCGGCCAGGCAGUCUCUGUCCUCCAGCCAAGUUUUCCCUCAUCAAAACGAUCUUCGCAGAUUCUGACAGGUGGAUUUUUUAUUACCUUUUGUCCUGACUCCCUGGCACUGAGCCCAUGCAGAGAAGAAAGGAAAGAACUUUCCAGGUUCCCUUCUACUGGAAUGCCCCCCCACUAGCCCUCUCACCUGCUCCCCAUUCCUCUACUUCUGGGAGCUCGGGAGGGUGGAGCAGCUUCUAGAGUCCAGGAGCUUCCCCUGCCACUGCCACAACCCCCGAUUCCACCACAGCCAUCGCCACUGCCACCUGCCUCCCGCUGAAUCUUGGCUCUUGUCUUCUCUUUCCAGCCCAGGUGAAGCCUCUGGGCUUCCUGAAGCCCUUCUCCUUGAUGAAGGCUUCCAGCCGCUUCAAGGCACACCAGGAUGCACUGCCACGGCUGCCCGUGCCCCCUCUCCAGCAGUCCCUGGACCACUACCUGAAGGCGCUGCAGCCCAUCGUGAGUGAGGAGGAGUGGGCCCACACCAAGCAGCUGGUGGAUGAGUUUCAGGCCUCAGGAGGUGUAGGGGAGCGCCUGCAGAAGGGGCUGGAGCGUCGGGCCAGGAAGACGGAGAACUGGCUGUCUGAGUGGUGGCUCAAGACCGCCUACCUCCAGUACCGCCAGCCUGUGGUCAUCUACUCGAGCCCAGGCGUGAUGCUACCCAAGCAGGACUUCGUGGACCUGCAGGGUCAGCUCCGAUUUGCUGCCAAACUCAUUGAGGGUGUGUUGGAUUUCAAGGUCAUGAUUGACAACGAGACCCUGCCCGUGGAGUACCUGGGGGGGAAGCCACUGUGCAUGAACCAGUACUAUCAGAUCUUGUCCUCCUGCCGAGUGCCGGGCCCCAAGCAGGACACAGUCAGCAACUUCAGCAAGACCAAGAAGCCUCCCACGCACAUCACCGUGGUACACAACUACCAGUUUUUUGAGCUGGAUGUGUACCACAGUGACGGGACACCCCUCACUGCGGAUCAGAUCUUUGUGCAGCUGGAGAAGAUCUGGAACUCAUCCCUACAGACCAACAAGGAGCCUGUGGGCAUCCUCACCUCCAACCACCGCAACUCCUGGGCCAAGGCAUACAACACCCUCAUCAAAGACAAGGUGAACCGGGAUUCCGUGCGCUCCAUCCAGAAGAGCAUCUUCACCGUGUGCCUAGAUGCAACCAUGCCCAGGGUCUCAGAAGACGUGUACCGCAGCCACGUGGCAGGCCAGAUGCUGCAUGGGGGCGGCAGCAGGCUCAACAGCGGCAACCGCUGGUUCGACAAGACGCUGCAGUUCAUCGUGGCAGAAGAUGGCUCCUGUGGGCUUGUGUACGAGCAUGCUGCAGCGGAGGGGCCCCCUAUUGUCACCCUUCUGGACUAUGUCAUCGAGUACACGAAGAAACCCGAGCUUGUGCGGUCUCCCCUGGUGCCCCUGCCCAUGCCCAAGAAGCUGCGGUUCAACAUCACCCCCGAGAUCAAGAGCGACAUCGAGAAGGCCAAGCAGAACCUCAGCAUCAUGAUCCAGGACCUGGAUAUCACCGUGAUGGUGUUCCACCAUUUUGGAAAAGACUUCCCCAAGUCGGAGAAGCUAAGCCCAGAUGCCUUCAUCCAGAUGGCUUUGCAGCUGGCCUACUACAGGAUCUACGGACAGGCAUGUGCCACCUAUGAAAGUGCCUCCCUGCGCAUGUUUCACCUGGGCCGCACCGACACCAUCCGCUCGGCUUCCAUGGACUCACUCACCUUUGUCAAGGCCAUGGAUGACUCCAGCGUCACGGAGCACCAGAAGGUGGAGCUGCUGCGGAAGGCCGUGCAGGCCCACCGAGGCUACACCGACCGGGCCAUCCGCGGGGAGGCCUUUGAUCGACACCUGCUGGGCCUGAAGCUGCAGGCCAUCGAGGACCUGGUGAGCAUGCCCGACAUCUUCAUGGACACCUCCUACGCCAUCGCCAUGCACUUCCACCUCUCCACCAGCCAGGUCCCUGCCAAGACAGACUGUGUCAUGUUCUUCGGGCCCGUGGUCCCCGACGGCUACGGUGUCUGCUAUAACCCCAUGGAGGCCCACAUCAACUUCUCCCUGUCGGCCUACAACAGCUGCGCGGAGACCAACGCCGCCCGCCUGGCGCAUUACCUGGAGAAGGCGCUCCUGGACAUGCGUGCCCUGCUGCAGAGCCACCCCCGGGCCAAGCUCUGAGCCCCUAGGACUCAGGCCUGCCAAUGCCACAGCCAAGCCCACCCUGGGAUGGGCCACCCACCAGGGCUCAGCUCCUUGGUUCCCUCUUCCUUGGUUCCCUCUUCCCUGGUCCCCCCAAAUCUACUGAGCCACGGACCGCAUCCUCCAGGGGGCCUGCAGGCCCCAGCCAAGUGCCUUCCGUGGGUCAUCCCAGCACCUGCCAGGGCCCGACCUGGGGCUGAGUGCAGAGGCUGAGCAGGACGUUAGGCCCGGGCCCCUGGCACGUCCUCCACCGGUGCCUCCUCUGGGGAAGGGAACCAGCCCUCCAGAGCAGGAGACUGGCAAGAGCUCUUUGUCUCACCAGCUCAGCCCCGGCCACUCCCUGCCAACUCCAUGACCAGGCCACCAUCUGUACCCUGCUUCCCAAACUCCCAGGACCUGGAGACAGGAUUGUCUGGGGCCGAGGGGCCAGGGUGUGAGGUUUCACCUCCGUUGCGGCUGUGCUCCUGUGGAUAACAUUGCUAGCGAGCCGCCUCUGGUUCCACUCAGCUUGGUUCCUGCCCCCGCCCUGCUGUAUGAUAUUAAUGUGGAAGGUCAUCAAUAAAGGGGAAUUGUGUUGGUGAA